GGUUUCACCAUGUUGGCCAGGCUGGUUUCGAACUUCUGACGUCAAGUGAUCUGUCCGCUUUGGCCUCCCAACGUGCUGGGAUUGCAGGUGUGAGCCACUGUGCCCAGCCUCAUCUCGUGGCUUUAAACUUUACCCCCAUGGCCCCAUGGCCCCUGCAGACCUCUCCCCUGAACGCUACAGUCCUGUGUCCAGUUGACUCCUUAACUCUCUGCUGGGAGGAUGAACAGGCAUCUCCACCUUCAUGUGUCCAAAGCCAUGCAGGCGUCUUUCCUGUUCCUGGGCCGAGGUUGCUCCUGCCUCAAGGCGUUCAUGUGGGCUGUCCCUCUGCUGGAACUCGCUGGCCCCUCAGCUGCAGGAUUGACUUCUAAAGACUCUUGGUACGUGAGGAAGAAACCCGGAAGAGGAAGAGGAAAGCAAAGGAGUCAGGGAUGGCUCUUUCUCAGGGUCUAUUGACAUUCAGGGAUGUGGCCAUAGAAUUCUCUCAGGAAGAGUGGAAGUGCCUGGACCCUGCUCAGAGGACUCUAUACAGGGACGUGAUGCUGGAGAAUUAUAGGAACCUGGUCUCCCUGGAUAUCUCUUCCAAAUGCAUGAUGAAGGAGUUCUCAUCAACAGCACAAGGCAAUACAGAAGUGAUCCACACAGGGACAUUGCAAAGACAUGAACGUCAUCACAUUGGAGAUUUUUGCUUCCAGGAAAUGGAGAAAGAUAUUCAUGAUUUUGAGUUUCAGUGGAAAGAAGAUGAAAGAAAUAGCCAUGAAGCACCCAUGACAGAAAUCAAACAGUUGACGGGUAGUACAAACCGACAUGAUCAAAGGCAUGCUGGAAACAAGCCUAUUAAAGAUCAGCUUGGAUCAAGCUUUCAUUCGCAUCUGCCUGAACUCCACAUGUUUCAGACCGAAGGGAAAAUUGGUAAUCAAGUUGAGAAGUCUAUCAACAGUGCUUCGUUGGUUUCAACAUCCCAAAGAAUUUCUUGUAGGCCUAAAACCCACAUUUCUAAGAACUAUGGGAAUAAUUUCCUGAAUUCUUCAUUACUCACACAAAAGCAGGAAGUACACAUGAGAGAAAAAUCUUUCCAAUGUAAUGAGAGUGGCAAAGCCUUUAAUUAUAGCUCAGUCUUAAGGAAACAUCAGAUAAUCCAUUUAGGAGCGAAACAAUAUAAAUGUGAUGUGUGUGGCAAGGUCUUUAAUCAAAAGCGAUAUCUUGCAUGUCAUCGUAGAUGUCACACUGGCAAGAAACCUUACAAGUGUAAUGAUUGUGGCAAGACCUUCAGUCAGGAGUUAACCCUUACAUGCCAUCAUAGACUUCAUACUGGAGAGAAACAUUACAAGUGCAGUGAGUGUGGCAAGACCUUCAGUCGAAAUUCAGCCCUUGUAAUUCAUAAGGCAAUUCAUACUGGAGAGAAAUCUUACAAGUGUAAUGAAUGUGGCAAGACCUUCAGUCAAACGUCAUACCUUGUGUACCAUCGUAGACUUCAUACUGGAGAGAAACCUUACAAAUGUGAAGAAUGUGACAAAGCUUUCAGUUUCAAAUCAAACCUUGAAAGACAUAGGAAAAUUCAUACUGGAGAGAAACCUUACAAGUGUAAUGAAUGCAGCAGGACCUUUAGUCGGAAGUCAUCCCUUACACGCCAUCGUAGACUUCAUACUGGAGAGAAACCUUAUAAGUGUAAUGAUUGUGGCAAGACCUUCAGUCAGAUGUCAUCCCUUGUAUACCAUCGUAGACUUCAUACUGGAGAGAAACCUUACAAAUGUGAAGAAUGUGAUGAAGCUUUCAGUUUCAAAUCGAACCUUGAAAGACAUAGGAGAAUUCAUACUGGAGAGAAACCUUACAAGUGUAAUGAUUGUGGCAAGACCUUCAGUCAGACAUCAUCCCUUGUAUACCAUCGUAGACUUCAUACUGGAGAGAAACCUUACAAAUGUGAAGAAUGUGAUGAAGCUUUCAGUUUCAAAUCAAACCUUGAAAGACAUAGGAUAAUUCAUACUGGAGAGAAACUUUACAAGUGUAAUGAAUGUGGCAAGACCUUUAGUCGGAAGUCAUCCCUUACACGCCAUUGUAGACUUCAUACUGGAGAGAAACCUUACCAGUGUAAUGAGUGUGGCAAAGCCUUUCGUGGGCAGUCAGCACUUAUUUACCAUCAAGCAAUCCAUGGUAUAGGGAAACUUUACAAAUGUAAUGAUUGUCACCAAGUCUUUAGUAAUGCUACAACCAUUGCAAAUCAUUGGAGAAUCCAUAAUGAAGAGAGAUCGUACAAGUGUAAUAGAUGUGGCAAAUUUUUCAGACAUCGUUCAUACCUUGCAGUUCAUUGGCGAACUCAUAGUGGAGAGAAACCUUACAAAUGUGAAGAAUGUGAUGAAGCUUUCAGUUUCAAAUCAAACCUUCAAAGACAUAGGAGAAUUCAUACUGGAGAGAAACCUUACAGGUGUAAUGAAUGUGGCAAGACCUUUAGUCGGAAGUCAUACCUUACAUGCCAUCGUAGACUUCAUACUGGAGAGAAACCUUACAAGUGUAAUGAGUGUGGCAAGACCUUCGGUCGAAAUUCAGCCCUUAUAAUUCACAAGGCAAUUCAUACUGGAGAGAAACCUUACAAGUGUAAUGAGUGUGGCAAGGCCUUCAGUCAGAAGUCAUCCCUUACAUGCCAUCUUAGACUUCAUACUGGAGAGAAACCUUACAAAUGUGAAGAAUGUGACAAAGUUUUCAGUCGCAAAUCAAGCCUUGAAAAACACAGGAGAAUUCAUACUGGAGAGAAACCAUACAAAUGUAAGGUUUGUGACAAAGCUUUUGGGCGUGAUUCACACCUGGCACAACAUACUAGAAUUCACACUGGAGAGAAACCUUACAAGUGUAAUGAAUGUGGCAAGAACUUCCGUCACAAUUCAGCCCUUGUAAUUCAUAAGGCAAUUCAUAGUGGAGAGAAACCUUACAAGUGUAAUGAGUGUGGCAAGACCUUCCGUCACAAUUCAGCCCUUGAAAUUCAUAAGGCAAUUCAUACUGGAGAAAAACCUUACAAGUGUAGUGAAUGUGGCAAGGUUUUUAAUAGAAAAGCAAACCUUUCACGUCAUCAUAGACUUCAUACUGGAGAGAAACCUUACAAGUGUAAUAAAUGUGGUAAGGUUUUUAAUCAACAAGCACACCUUGCAUGUCAUCAUAGAAUUCAUACUGGAGAGAAACCUUACAAGUGUAAUGAGUGUGGCAAAACCUUCCGUCACAAUUCAGUCCUUGUAAUUCAUAAGACAAUUCAUACUGGAGAGAAACCUUACAAGUGUAAUGAAUGUGGCAAGGUUUUUAAUCGAAAAGCAAAACUUGCACGUCAUCAUAGAAUUCAUACUGGAAAGAAACAUUAGAAAUAUGAAGAAUGUGACAAAGUUUACAGUUGUAAAUCAAGUCUUGAAAGACAGGAGAAUUCAUACUGGAGAGAAAGCUUACAAAUGUAAGAGUUUGUGACAAGAAUCUUGGGCGUGAUUCACACCUGGCCCAACAAACUAGAAGUCACACUGGAGAGAAACCUUACAAGUGUACUGAGUGUGGCAAAGCCUUUAGUGGGCAGUCAACACUUAUUCACCAUCAGGCAAUCCAUGGUAUAGGGAAACUUUACUAAUGUAAUGAUUAUCACAAAGUCUUCAGUAACACUACAACCGUUUCAAAUCAUUGGAGAAUCCAUAAUGAGAGAUUUUGAAAGUGUAAUAAAUGUGGCAAAUUUUUCAGACAUUGUUCAUACCUUGCAGUUCAUCGGUGAACUCAUGCUGGAGAGAAACCUUACAAAUGUCAUGAUUGUGGCAAGGUCUUCAGUCUAGCUUCAUCUUAUGCAAAACAGGAGACUUCAUACAGGAGACAAACUUCACAAGUAUGAUGAUUGCAGCAAAGCCUUUACUUCACGUUCACACCUAAUUAGACAUCAGAGAAUCCAUACUGGACAGAAAUCUUACAAAUGUCAUCAGUGUGGCAAGGUCUUCAGUCUGAGAUCACCCCUUAAGGAACAUCAGAAAAUUCAUUUUUGAGAUGAUUGUUCCAAAUGCAAUGAGUAUAGCAAACCAUCAAGCAUUAAUUGGCAUUAGAGUCAAUUCAGCAUUGACUUGAGUUUGAAUUGACUUAACAUUGAGUUCAAGCAUUAAUUGACAUUAAAGUGUUUAUGUUAAGAAGAUUGGGCCAGGCGGGGUGGCUCACGCCUGUAAUCCCAGCACUUUGGGAGGCCAAGACCAAUAGAUCACUUGAGGUCAGGAGUUUGAGACCAGACUGGCCAACAGACAUGAGUCACUUUUCCCACCCUGUAUUUUGUUUCUUUAAUAAAAACUGUUACGGGUUUUUAUGGGUAUCUGUUGAAUCUAAAUCACAUUUGUUUGUAUAAUCAUUCAACAAUAUUAAGACUUCCAAUCCAUCAAUAUGGGUUGUAUGUCUAUUUAGUUUUUUUGAUCAAUGUAGAUUUCAAGGUACAAGCUUCUCACCUCCUUAAUUCAGUUUAUUUGUAAGUAUUAAGUUUCAUAGCAAAUUGAAGUGUGUUCAUAAGUUUCUUUAAACAUUAUUUAUUGUUAAUGUAAGGAAAUUCAACUAAUUUUGGGUGCUGAUUUUGUAUUCUGCAAAUACAUUGAGUGGGUUUAUUAGUAUCAGUAAAAUCUUGGUUGAUUCUUUGUGAUUUUCUUUCUUUUUUUUUUGAGACAGUCUCACUCUGUUACCCAGGCUCUUUUCUUUUUUUUUGAGAAGGAGUCUCACUCUUGUCACUUGGACUGGAGUACAAUGGCACGAUCUUGGCUCACUGCAGCCUCUGCCUUUCGGGUUUAAGUGAUUCUCCUGCCUACUAACUGAGAUUACAGGUGCCUGCCACCAUGUCCGUAUAAUUUUUUUGUAUUUUUAGUAGAGACGGGGUUUCACCAUGUUGACCAGGUUUUUCUUGAACUCCUGACUUCAGGUGAUCCGCCCCCAUCAGCAUCCCAAAGUUCUGGGAUUACAGGUGUGAGCCACCGCACCCAGCCAGUGAUUUUCUAUAUAGAAUGUCGUAUCAUCUACAAGGAAAUAAUUUUUUUUUUUGAGACAAUGUCUCUCUCUGUCGCCAGGCUAGAGUGCCGUGGAAUGAUCUUUGCUCACUGCAACCUCUGUCUCCCACGUCCAAGCAAUUCUGUCUCAGCCUCCUGAGUAGCUGGGACUACAGGCGCAUGUCACCACACCUAGCUAAUUUAUUUAUUUUUUUUAUUUUAGUAAAGACGGGGUUUCACCAUGUUGGCCCAGAUGGUGGGCCAACAUGGUGAGUACCUUGAAGAGAACUUGAAAGAAUAUGUUAGAUCGCCUAACCUCAUUAUCCGCCCACUUCGGACUUGCAAAUUGCUGGGAUUAUGGGUGUGAGCCAUGAGCCCGGCCCCAACAAAUGUAAUUUUACUUCUGUCUUUCUGAUUUGGAUGAGUUUUAUUUCUUUUGCUAUUUAAUUGCUCUGCCUAGGACAGCCAGUAUUUAUUGAAUAUCAGGGGUGAGAGCAUUCUUGCAUCAUGUGAUAUCCUACAGGAAAACCAUUCCAUUUUCCUUCAUUGGUUAUUUCAGCUGUGGUCAUUUCAUGGAUGAUUUUUAUAUUUUUGAGGUAAAACUCUACCUAUAUUGUUUAGGAUUUUUACGAAGAAUGAAUAUUGAGUUCUGUGAAAUGCUUUUUCUCUAUCUAUUGAGAUAAUGUGUUUUUUAUCUGUCAUUCUGUGCAAGUGUGUAUCCCAUUGAUUUGAGUAUGUUGAACCAUCCUUGCAUCCCAUGAAUAGGUAGCACUUGGAUGUUUACAAUCCCUUUUUAUAUCCUCUUGAAUACAGUUUGCUAGUAUAAGGGUCUUCAAGAAGUUCAUGGAAAAAUACAUAUUAUGAAAAAUUUGUGCAUAAAUUUCACACUUUUUGUACCAAAAUAAACCAGUAUAAACUUGUUAUAACGUCUGAACAGGCUCUAGUUUGAGGCACUCAGAAGGAUAAGACAUCAGUUUGAAAAGAACCUCUAUCACAGCAAUACAAAUUCUGUUAAAACAAGAAGAAACAUCAAAUUUACGAUGAGACCAGACGCAGUGGCUCAGGCCUGUAAUCCCAGCGGUUUUAGAGGCCCAGGCAGGUGGGUGACGUGAGCCUAGGGAUUCAAGACCAGCCUGGGCGACAUAGGGGACCUCUUCUCUGCUAAAAGUAAAAAAAGUCAGCCAGGUGUGGUGGUGCACUGCUGUGGUCCCAGCUACUCUGGGCACUGAAGUGGGAGGAUCAGUUGAAGCAGGGAUUUUGAGGCUGAAGUGAGCCCUGAUCUCACCACUGCACUCCAGCCUGGGUGACAGAGCUAGACCCUGUCUCAAACAAGCAAAUAAAUGAGAGGCAUAAUUCCUCCUUUGAGAAUAAAGGAAAAGAUUUCCCUUCCUUUUGUCUCUUUUCUCAGGACGUUUAUUUAGAAAAUUUGUAAAUGAGGCCGGGCGUGGUGGCUCACGCCUGUAAUCCCAGCACUUUGGGAGGCUAAGGUGGGCGGAUCACGAGGUCAGGAGAUCGAGACCAUCCUGGCUAACACGGUGAAACCCCGUCUCUACUAAAAAUACAAAAAAUUAGCUGGGCGAGGUGGCAGGCACCUGUAGUCCCAGCUACUCGGGAGGUUGAGGCAGGAGAAUGGCGUGAACCCAGGGGGGCGGAACCUGCAGUGAGCCGAGAUCGCACCACUGCACUCCAGCCUGG